AGAAGGGGUUGUUUUGCUUUUGCUUAUUUCCGUCCAUUUCCCUCUCUGCGCGCGGACCUUCCUUUUCCAGAUGGUGAGAGCCGCGGGGACACCCGACGCCGGGGCAGGCUGAUCCACGAUCCUGGGUGUGCGUAACGCCGCCUGGGGCUCCGUGGGCGAGGGACGUGUGGGGACAGGUGCACCGGAAACUGCCAGACUGGAGAGUUGAGGCAUCGGAGGCGCGAGAACAGCACUACUACUGCGGCGAGACGAGCGCGGCGCAUCCCAAAGCCCGGCCAAAUGCGCUCGUCCCUGGGAGGGGAGGGAGGCGCGCCUGGAGCGGGGACAGUCUUGGUCCGCGCCCUCCUCCCGGGUCUGUGCCGGGACCCGGGACCCGGGAGCCGUCGCAGGUCUCGGUCCAAGGGGCCCCUUUUCUCGGAAGGGCGGCGGCCAAGAGCAGGGAAGGUGGAUCUCAGGUAGCGAGUCUGGGCUUCGGGGACGGCGGGGAGGGGAGCCGGACGGGAGGAUGAGCUCCCCUGGCACCGAGAGCGCGGGAAAGAGCCUGCAGUACCGAGUGGACCACCUGCUGAGCGCCGUGGAGAAUGAGCUGCAGGCGGGCAGCGAGAAGGGCGACCCCACAGAGCGCGAACUGCGCGUGGGCCUGGAGGAGAGCGAGCUGUGGCUGCGCUUCAAGGAGCUCACCAAUGAGAUGAUCGUGACCAAGAACGGCAGGAGGAUGUUUCCGGUGCUGAAGGUGAACGUGUCUGGCCUGGACCCCAACGCCAUGUACUCCUUCCUGCUGGACUUCGUGGCGGCGGACAACCACCGCUGGAAGUACGUGAACGGGGAAUGGGUGCCGGGGGGCAAGCCGGAGCCGCAGGCGCCCAGCUGCGUCUACAUCCACCCCGACUCGCCCAACUUCGGGGCCCACUGGAUGAAGGCUCCCGUCUCCUUCAGCAAAGUCAAGCUCACCAACAAGCUCAACGGAGGGGGCCAGAUCAUGCUGAACUCCUUGCAUAAGUAUGAGCCUCGAAUCCACAUAGUGAGAGUUGGGGGUCCACAGCGCAUGAUCACCAGCCACUGCUUCCCUGAGACCCAGUUCAUAGCGGUGACUGCUUAUCAGAACGAGGAGAUCACAGCUCUUAAAAUUAAGUACAAUCCAUUUGCAAAAGCUUUCCUUGAUGCAAAGGAAAGAAGUGAUCACAAAGAGAUGAUGGAGGAACCCGGAGACAGCCAGCAACCUGGGUACUCCCAAUGGGGGUGGCUUCUUCCUGGAACCAGCACCCUGUGUCCACCUGCAAAUCCUCAUCCUCAGUUUGGAGGUGCCCUCUCCCUCCCCUCCACGCACAGCUGUGACAGGUACCCAACCCUGAGGAGCCACCGGUCCUCACCCUACCCCAGCCCCUAUGCUCAUCGGAACAAUUCUCCAACCUAUUCUGACAACUCACCUGCAUGUUUAUCCAUGCUGCAAUCCCAUGACAAUUGGUCCAGCCUUGGAAUGCCUGCCCAUCCCAGCAUGCUCCCCGUGAGCCACAAUGCCAGCCCACCUACCAGCUCCAGUCAGUACCCCAGCCUGUGGUCUGUGAGCAACGGCGCCGUCACCCCGGGCUCCCAGGCAGCAGCCGUGUCCAACGGGCUGGGGGCCCAGUUCUUCCGGGGCUCCCCCGCGCACUACACACCCCUCACCCAUCCGGUCUCGGCGCCCUCUUCCUCGGGAUCCCCACUGUACGAAGGGGCGGCCGCGGCCACAGACAUCGUGGACAGCCAGUACGACGCCGCAGCCCAAGGCCGCCUCAUAGCCUCAUGGACACCUGUGUCGCCACCUUCCAUGUGAAGCAGCAAGGCCCAGGUCCCGAAAGAUGCAGUGACUUUUUGUCGUGGCAGCCAGUGGUGACUGGAUUGACCUACUAGGUACCCAGUGGCAGUCUCAGGUUAAGAAGGAAAUGCAGCCUCAGUAACUUCCUUUUCAAAGCAGUGGAGGAGCACACGGCACCUUUCCCCAGAGCCCCAGCAUCCCUUGCUCACACCUGCAGUAGCGGUGCUGUCCCAGGUGGCUUACAGAUGAACCCAACUGUGGAGAUGAUGCAGUUGGCCCAACCUCACUGACGGUGAAAAAAUGUUUGCCAGGGUCCAGAAACUUUUUUUGGUUUAUUUCUCAUACAGUGUAUUGGCAACUUUGGCACACCAGAAUUUGUAAACUCCACCAGUCCUACUUUAGUGAGAUAAAAAGCACACUCUUAAUCUUCUUCCUUGUUGCUUUCAAGUAGUUAGAGUUGAGCUGUUAAGGACAGAAUAAAAUCAUAGUUGAGGACAGCAGGUUUUAGUUGAAUUGAAAAUUUGACUGCUCUGCCCCCUAGAAUGUGUGUAUUUUAAGCAUAUGUAGCUAAUCUCUUGUGUUGUUAAACUAUAACUGUUUCAUAUUUUUCUUUUGACAAAGUAGCCAAAGACAAUCAGCAGAAAGCAUUUUCUGCAAAAUAAACGCAAUAUGCAAAA